GACAGGCUCUGAGGUGCUGCUGUGGCGGCGUCCGCGGGGCUGAGGCGGGUGGGAGCCGGAGCCGAGCGCGGGCUGAGGGAGGAGGGCGGCGACUGGAGAGCGGCGAGCGGCGAGCAGCGCAGGACGCAGAGCCUCUUUCACUUUUUCCCUGCUGAGUGCCCCCUCCCACCCCUCCCACUCCACACACACCCUGUUUGCCCGUGAGCCUGGGGAACUUGCAGCUUAAAGCCAGCCACCCCCACGGCAACAUGUACCCCAGCAACAAGAAGAAAAAGGUGUGGAGAGAGGAGAAACAUGAAGUGGAAUGGCUCAUUAAGAAUAAAAUAGCUUUGUUCAUUCCUUUUCAUUCUUUUUUAAAAAAUGUUUUUUCUUAGUGAACUAA